CUUCGGGACUCCGCCCCGCGCGCGGACCUGCAGCCAUGGCAGUCACCGCCCAGGCAGCCCGCAGGAAGGAGCGCGUCCUCUGCCUGUUUGACGUGGACGGGACCCUCACGCCGGCUCGCCAGUCGUGGAGCAGAGAGGGCUUCUUUUCAAAUUCGUUUAUGAGCUCUACCCACCCGGAUGUGAGAGGCUCCAGGCCUAGCCUGUUUGCUGUGAGGACACUGAGGAAUAGUGAGGGUCCCGAAUGCCCCUCCCCAUCCUCUGUGGUGAAGUUGCCCUGGCUUGGGCCCUGGAGGCCUUCCUGCAGGGGUGGAUCCGGGAGGAAGAUAGCAGGACUGGAGCAAAGAAAAUUGACCCUGAGGUGGCCGCCUUCCUGCAGAAGCUACGAAGUAGAGUGCAGAUCGGUGUGGUGGGCGGCUCUGACUACUGUAAGAUCGCUGAGCAGCUGGGUGACGGGGAUGAAGUCAUUGAGAAGUUUGAUUAUGUGUUUGCCGAGAACGGGACGGUGCAGUAUAAGCACGGACGACUGCUCUCCAAGCAGUGGAACCUUCAUCGAGUUCCGGAAUGGCAUGCUGAACAUCUCGCCCAUCGGCCGGAGCUGCACCCUGGAGGAGAGGAUCGAGUUCUCCGAACUGGACAAGAAAGAGAAGAUCCGGGAGAAGUUCGUGGAAGCCCUGAAAACAGAGUUUGCUGGCAAAGGGCUGAGGUUCUCUCGAGGAGGCAUGAUCAGCUUUGACGUCUUCCCCGAGGGCUGGGACAAGCGCUACUGCCUGGAUAGCCUGGACCAGGACAGCUUCGACACCAUCCACUUCUUUGGGAACGAGACUAGCCCUGGUGGGAACGACUUUGAGAUCUUUGCCGACCCCCGGACUGUUGGCCACAGCGUGGUGUCUCCUCAGGACACGGUGCAGCGAUGCCGGGAGAUUUUCUUCCCAGAGACAGCUCAUGAGGCGUGACCGGGGCCCACAUCUGUGUGUCGUGACUUCUGAAGAGUUUGGCCUAGGCCUAAAGAGAGGUCCUGGUGUUGGAUAGAUGCCAGGGCCCCUCCUCUGGCCCAGGACGCCUGCUGCAAGCCCACCCAGAUGGGGCCAGAGUCUGUGUGGACAACCGUCCCCAGCCAGUCUGCUCCUAGUGGCACUGGCUUCGUCCUCCCAGGGCCCAGAGUGUUCCCCAUGCUCCACCUGGUGGCCCAGGCCACAGCUGCUGCUUGUAUUUCGGUACAGAAGAGGUUUCUUUCUGCACCAGGAGGAGGCGUGCUCAAGUAUCGGUACGAGAUCUAGCCUGCCCUGCCUGCCUGCCCUGGGCGAUGAGGUACGGUGGGGAAGGUGCCUAUUUUAGAGAACUUUGUCACAGUAUUAAAGUUCCCAGAACAAA